GCAGAUCCCUGCAGCCCGGCAGGAGAGAAGGCUGAGCCUUCUGGCGUCAUGGAGAGGCUCGUCCUAACCCUGUGCACCCUCCCGCUGGCUGUGGCGUCUGCUGGCUGCGCCACGACGCCAGCUCGCAACCUGAGCUGCUACCAGUGCUUCAAGGUCAGCAGCUGGACGGAGUGCCCGCCCACCUGGUGCAGCCCGCUGGACCAAGUCUGCAUCUCCAACGAGGUGGUCGUCUCUUUUAAAUGGAGUGUACGCGUCCUGCUCAGCAAACGCUGUGCUCCCAGAUGUCCCAACGACAACAUGAAGUUCGAAUGGUCGCCGGCCCCCAUGGUGCAAGGCGUGAUCACCAGGCGCUGCUGUUCCUGGGCUCUCUGCAACAGGGCACUGACCCCACAGGAGGGGCGCUGGGCCCUGCGAGGGGGGCUCCUGCUCCAGGUGGGCCUCAGCCUCCUCAGGGCCCUGUUGUGAGGGCCCUCCCUUUACGCCCCCUCCUGGCCCUGCUGGCCCAUCCCGUCUCCUGCCUCCAACUGCCAUCCUGCCUCCGCCCCUUCCAGGACACUGGGGGGGGACCCUCCCUCUCUGAGGUGGUGGGGAGGGUGCCAUUGCCUCCAUCCCGGAUCUAGCCACCUCACUCCUCCCCACCGGGGGCCCCUUUGCUGGAGAACCCCAAGGAUUCAGCAACUGCUCCUCCUGGGGAAGGACAGUGCCUCUGAUGUGGGUGAUGGGAAGGACGGUGCCUCUGAUGUGGGUGAUGGGAAGGACGGUGCCUCUGGUGUGGGUGAUGGGAAGGACGGUGCCUCUGGUGUGGGUGAUGGGAUGGACGGUGCCUCUGGUGUGGGUGAUGGGAAGGACGGUGCCUCUGGUGUGGGUGAUGAGAAGGACGGUGCCUCCGGUGUGGGUGAUGGGAAGGACGGUACCUCCGGUGUGGGUGACGGGAAGAAUGGUGCCUCCAGUGUGGGUGAUGGGAAGGAUGGUGCCUCUGAUGGGCAAUGGGGAAGGAUGGUGCCUCCGGUGUUGGGUGAUGGGGAAGGACGGUGCCUCUGGUGUUGGUGGUGGGAAAGACAGUGUCUCUGGUGGGCGAUGGCCCCUUGCAUGAGGCCCCUUGCCCUGAAUGCUGUCCAGGACCCUUCGAGGGGCAGAAGAACCUGGGUGCGGCCACAGCUGGGGCUCCCACUCUGCCUUCCCAUUUCCAGCCCCCUCUGCCCAAGGGAAACCCAGGAAGGAUAACACUGUGGGUGCCCCCACCUGUGCAUUGGGACCACGACCUUCACCCUCUUGGAGACAAUAAACUCUCAUGCCCCCA